GAGGGACCUCUGCAGUGGAUGUGUUCCUGGCGGCUGGCCCUAGAGACACUGCACUCUGAGCCAACCGUGAAGUCAUUUUGAAUUUAAGGAGUCUUGCUAAUCCAAGGCAAUGUGUCUUAAUUUGACAAAGUAAAGGCUGCCCGAUAAGCAAGCCUCACUACAAGUUCUGUGAAACAGGGGGUGUUUGUAAGUUUAGAUUGUGCUAGAGAAAUGUGGUGAUGUGGAAGAACGGGCUCAUUUUCUCCUGUUUACUCCCUUUCCCACCCCAUCCCCCUCCUCUCUCCCUUCUCUCUUACUUACUUUGGCCCAAAUCAGCCCUGCAGUCUGGCCUCUGCAGUGGCUUGAUGUGAAAUUUGAGAAACAUAUGUAGUUUUCUAUUUCAGGAAAAUGAUCUCAGGGAUUGAAUGUGUUUUUUUGUUGGCUGUUAAGCUCUGAUCUUGCCCAGUGUGGUUUUUUGAUGAUGGGAAAGAGGCUUCGAAGUGCUUUUUAUCAGAAUUUCAUGUAAUAAAACUUAAGGUUUGGUUUCUUUAUUUUGGCCCCCAACCCCCUCCCAGGCUCAGGACACAAUGUCGUCUAUUCUGUCAGAAGUGGGAAGAAGUACACAUUGUUCAUAUUACAAUCACUUCUUUGCUGCUUGCACACACAUAUAUAAGAAUGGCCACUGUGUCUAUCCUUCACAAAAGCUAUUUUAAAUGUAGUUCAGUGGAGGACCAAAGGUCUGCGUAGUGUCUCUUACAAAGGAAAAGGGAUCUGUUGGGGGAAAAGUCUGCCUUUGUUUUGCCUUGGAAGGGCCAGUAUUUUUCUUUGUUCUAGAGGUGAGUGCCAAUAAUGGGCCUAGUGCCCUAUCAAGCAAACUUCAUUAAUCCAGCCCUGCAAAGGGUACACUGAUCAGAUAAAAGGGACCUACAUCCUCAAAGCUCAAGGUAUUUGUUUUUAAACUUUUUUCUUACUGUAAAUAAAUAUCACUAUUGUACUUAAUCUCAUAUUCAUAAUUGUAUUCCUUUUCUUAAAGAGCCUUUACAUAAAAGCUUCAGGCCCUACAAAAUCCGAGAGCAUCCUUCAUGGAGGAAGGAUAGUAGACUCGAGGGUGAGUGGUUGAACUUUGGCUCUGGUGUAAAAUGCCCACCCUGGGACUUAUUGUGUGACCUUGAGCACGUUACAUACCAUUUCUGCACUUCAUUGUCUUAUUUAUAUUUCAUGGGCUUGUUGCGGGAUUGAACAGGUUCAAGUGUAUAAAGCUCAUAGUACAACCUGCUAAGGACUCAACAUUAGCUAUUCCUGCUGCUGUUUUUAUUAUUUGUUGCUGGCGUAUAAGACCUAGGCAAAUGGAGCUAAAUACUAUUGUCUACCAUUAAAAUAUUCACCUUCUGGAGGGAAUAGUGCAAGGGUAACUUCAGAUUUGCAUUGAAAAACCCAUGGACUAUCACUUUACAUAUUUAUUUCCUUACCAUCUUCAACCCUUAUCCAGACAGCUCCAAAUGCACAUUAUUCAGAAAAUUGGUGAUAUUUUCACAGCACUGAGACUAAGCUCAUCUCCUGCUGGUCCUUAUCACUCACCAGCCUUUCAGCCACAUCAGACAUCUCCUCAAUCUCUGGGCAAACCAGGCCUUUUCAUGUCUUCUUGACUUUGCACGUACUGUUUCCUCCCCGCAGAGUAUCAUUUGCCCUUUUUUCUGCUUGUCAACUGCUAUUCACCCUUCGAGACCCAACUUAAAUAUUAUUUGUGAAUUUUGGGCAGUUACACAGACUCUUUUGGGCAGUUACACACUACUGUUUCAUUUUUCCUAUAGUUCUUCAAGAACUUCUCUCAUUGUAGUGUAAUUAUUUCUUGACAUACAUUUUUCUUCUAACAGCCUAGGAGGUCUUUGGAUGAAGAUACUACAGUCUAUUCACUUUUAUAACCCCGGUACAGAGUGCAUGACACGUGUUAGGUGUUGAGAAAUCUGAGAAAUCGACUGGGAAGAGUUUUUUUUCAUACCAUUAUAUUUUAAAAGCUGCAAUAGUUUGUUCCAGAAAAGUUAUAUUUUUCCCUUGGUGUAUAUUCUAAUUUAAAAGGUGUUUUUAAUGCCUGAUUGAUCUCCAAUCUGUAAUGACUUUGUAGCAUUUUCUUUGUUUCCCUGCAUUCAGCCUUCUGAUUUAAGCAGAUAAUGCUUGGAAACACCUGUUUAAGUUGUAUCUUCUUUGCUAGUUGUAACUUCAUGAGUACAGGGACCAUAUAUGUUCUGUUCACAGCUCUAUCCCCAAGUCCUAAUACAGUGGUUGGCAGUUCUAGAGGUAGAAGAAAUUAUAAUAAUAAUAGUGCUUGUAUUUUAUGCUUAACAGAGCACUUAACAUGCUGGCCACUAUUGUGAGUAUUUUAGAUACAUUAACCCCUUCAGUCCUCCCAAUAUUCUUAUGUUAUAUGUAUUAUAAUUAUCAUCUGUUUUCUACAGAUAAAGAAACAGACUCAAAAGAGGCUAAGGAACUUGCCGGUGGUCACACAAUGAUUGGCAGAGUUGGGAUUUUAACCUGGGCAGUCUGGCUCCAGAAUUCAGGCUGUUUGCCAUAAUGGUUCCUUGCCUCUGAUUAGUACUAAUUAGCUUAGUACUUGUUUGUUAACUAAUUAUUAAAGGAAUCCAACAGAGACCUAUUUCUCUAAUGUAAAGAGUUCAUUCAUUAGGCAAAUAAUCACCCUAAGCCAGUUGUUCUGGAAGUAUGGCCUUCAGACCAGCAGCAUGAGCAGCGUCACUUGGAAAUACAUUGGAAAUGCAAAUUCUGUGGCCUCACUCCCACCCUACUCAAUCAGAAACUCUUGGGAGUGGGACCAAAUAAUUUGUGUUUUAAAAAAAUCCUCCAGAAGAAUCUGAUGGAUGCUAAAGUUUGAGAACCACUGGCCAAGACUCAGCCAUUUUCUCUGGAAUUUUACCCCUGAUUUUUGCUUUUCUUAAGAAGUCAUAAUUUUGGGUGUCUCACUUUUGCAUACUCCUGAUUUUUGUGACAUUAAUGUGGGGACUAAGCUCUAACCUCAGUGAAUGUUUUUGCUAAAGUUUCUGAGAAAUUUUGAAGGUUUCAGGUGUGUCUGUAGCUUGACAGUGUUUGUUUCUUUUGAUUUUUUUUUCCUGUGAUAGCUUUUAGGAUCAGGAAAUUUAAAAAAUAUAGUACCUCCUCCAUUCAGCCCUGCUGUCUCAGACUCCCCUAACUGGUGAGUGAAGAAGGAGCCCAGAGGUGCAGGGAUAACAGAGAAAGGGGAAGUAGCAGAAUCAGUGAGUGGGGAAUCAAAGUUUGAUGUUAUCGCACUUCCUAGAAGUGGCCUCAGGUCCUUUGGACUGUUGGUUUACAAAUGGUAGAAAAAAGGGACACUGGACUUCAAACUGGACUUGGAAUCCCAGUUCAGUCUCUCUAUCUAUGUGAUUCUAGGAAAGUAAUUUUUCUGAGCAACAGUUCCCUCAUCUUUAAAAUGGGGAUAAUAUUACUAAUGUUUUAAUGAUGUGAGAAUUUAUGGAGAUGCAUGAUGAGCACUCAAUUCAUGCUUGUUGUAUCUAUACUGAAGGAAGCUGUAAGAGAUAGAGUUAGUCACUAGCAUAUUUACCAGUGAGUGUUCUAAGAAAUGGAUUAUAGAUUUUGCAGAGCAACAAGGAAUCCACAGCAUUCCACAAUGGCUGGUAUUCCAAGGAUCGAAAUUCUGGGAGGUUCAGUUGCAGAGAAAACUAGGCACCAGUUUGAAUGCAUUAUGUCUUGAGUCUGCUUUUUUUUUUUUUUUAAAAGAAAGGUAUCUAAAAGUGAUUUAACAAUGUCAGGAUUUAGACUUAAGUUUUUUUCUGUUAAAGAGGCCAUUGCUGAAAGUCAAGACCCAAGGACUGUACAAAUAUUGAUGCAACUGUCAGAGAUACAUGGUAUUUGACCUUCUAUUAAUAAAGACAAAUUAUUGCAUUUCUGUGAUAUUUGAGUCUGCAGGAACUUCCCUUAAUUCCACUGGUAUUCCAUUCCACGGCUACCAGGGCUGCUGGGACAAGGGACGUGGCGUUGUGUUUCUGAUUUACGAGGUGGAAUAUUAGUCUGAUUUACUAAACUGAAAGAGCAGGUUCAGAUAACAAACAACAUAGUGAAACUUCCUGAAUAACAGCCACAGAAACAACUCAUGUAUUUGGUGGUAUCACAACAAGUUUGGCUAGAUUUAUCCACAGACUAGAAUACAAACCAUGGAGGAAAGAAAGCAGGUAAGCACAAGUAAAUAGAGGGCAAGGCAGAUACUAGUGGACUAUACUGGAUGUAGGAAGACUUUGAGGAAGGCUUUUUUUUGCAGACAUCUGCAGGGUGUAGGCAGUGAAGUGUUUGUUGUGACUAUUUGCCAGCACCAUCCCACUUCACAGGUGGGUGGGUGGUUCCUUUUCACCAAGAUUUUAAUGGCAGGUUGUGCCCCAUAAAAGGGCGGGGCAGUAUACCCUGUAUUAGUUUAAAAAAGGUCUCAGCUUACACGGGACAGCAUUUUUACUUUUUACCCUUGCCUUUGCUCAUUCACAGGGAGUACUUCGGAAUCAGCCCAUCUAAGCCUCAGACUUCAAAGGGAGCUCAUUCCUAUUUGACAACAGUCAUAUCCAUUUUGCCAACUCUUUGACCUUUGAAAUAGCAUCUACUCAGUCAGGUCUGACCUGUCAACUGUCUGUAAAAACCCAUCCAGAUCAAGAACUUGAUAUUUUCAAGAACACAUCUAAAGGAUGGGGGCCCUUCUAAUUUUGUUUCUCCAGGACUUGUUUUGGGAGAAGCCAGCUGCUUCUUCUGGUCUUAAUGGGAUGGGAUUAUAGAUGGGUUGAGUCUGUGAGGCCUCAACUUACAUGAUGAUCCUGUGUCCUUUUAUUAUAGGUUGCACAUGUUUUAGCCACUCAUGGCAGCAUUUUUCUCCAGCUACAGUCAAUUUUGUCUAAUUAUUGUUGAUCAUGAUUUUACUGUAAAAAAAAAUUUUUUUUUUUGAGACAUGGUUUCACUCAGUCAGUCUGGAUUGUGCAGUGGCACAGUCUCAGUGCACUGCAACCUCUGCUUCCCAGGCUCAAUCGAUUUUCCUGCCUCAGUCUCCUGAGUAGCUGGGACUACAGGUGCACGCCACCACGCCUGGCUAAUUUUUGUAUUUUUAGUAGAGAUGGUGUUUCACCAUAUUGGCCAGGCUGGUCUUGAACUCCUAACCUCAAAUGAUCCACCUGCCUCAGCCUUCCAAAGUUCUGGUAUUACAGGCAUGAGCCACCAUGCCCAGGUUGUAAAAGUAUUUUUAAAAAGUGUUUUCAGAGGCCAUUUGCCAUGGGAAAAUGGGAUAUGUUGACCUUCCUGUUUACCUCCAUUUGUGGGCUUUUGGUUGUGAGCAUCAGUUCAUAUCCAGUUUUGGGGACCACUCUUGGGUAUACUUUAAAUAAUUCAGAUGUUGAAAUUUUUCAGAAUGAGAAAAUCUAGAGAGAAGUCCAGUUUGAUUAUACUAGAACCUCAUUUGCUGAUUAAAUUGUAAAAUUCCUAAUUGCAACUUGGUCAUGUCUUUGCAAAAUAGUAAUAAUAAUAUUAACUUCUAUUUAUAUAGUGACUGUCUUCUCAAAGAACUCAAAACAGUGUCCUUUUCUGUAUCCCUGCUAUUCCCAAAACAUGUUUGUGGCAAUGUAUGUGGCUUCAAAAUGUGGAUGUAUCAUUAUGAAAUAUAAAUGCAUGUGGUGAUGGUAUUUAUUAGAAUCAUAUGUUAUUGGAAGUACCUAACAUUGGGUGUAAAGGAAGCCUGGUCAAGUUUCCAAUAGAGAUUUACAAUUGGGCCUCUUUGUAUCUCAGUUUCUUCAUCUGUAUAGUGGGCAUAAUAGUUCCUAUUUUAUAGAGUUAUUGUGAUGAUUGUGUUAAUACAUUUAAAGCAUUGACACAGUAAUGCUGGGAUAGUCCUCAAAUGCUAUUGUUUGCAUCGGUUUUAGAAUCAGUCUAAUAAAUAUGAGUUUAAAUACCCCUUUGUCCCUUGCUUGUUGUGUCGUCUUGGGCAAUAACAGUAACAGUCAACACAGAUGCUAUUUAUUGAAUAAUACUUAUAUGUCAGGCAUUAUAUUAGGCCCAGGAUAUAAGUGAUUAUUUAUCACUUAUUCCUUUAACUUUCUUAAAUAGGUAUGAUUAUACUCAUUUUAUAGAUGAGUUAGGUAAGGUUUAGAGAAGUUAAGAAACUUUCCCAUAGUAACAGAGUUAGAUUACUGGCAAAGCGGACUCUCUGAAUUCUUGUUUUUGGUUACCUACUUAGGUUCCCCUGAACCACAGUUUCAUCAUUUGUAAUAGGGAUGACAAUAGCUCUUUGUAAGGAUUAAAUAUUGUACAUAAAGUAUCUAGCACUUACUGUGCAUUCUUGACAUGAUAUACAAUGAUAUUAUCCUCUCCAAUUAGAGCUUUCCAUAUAAUAUAAUUUUUUUCUUUGUGUUCCUUAUGCCAUGCAUAUAUCUUUAGAGAUUAAAAGACACUUCUUAAGAAUGGAUUCUUGCAUUUCUGAGAACUUCAGAAUCACACUUGUGAUCUGACACAGUAUAUAUACACUCAGGUAUUGAUGUGUGUAUGUGUACUUUCCAUUCUGUUCAGUCUAGAAGUGUAUAGAUGCUCAAUCUGGGUGCUUUGUAAGGAACAUCACAAAUGUUCAAAAUCGUGGAUGGACUUGAACAUGAAAAUGCCUUGGCCUCAAAGUUUUGCUUUUCUGUUCUCAAAGUUGUUGAGGAAACUGGCUUAGUUAAAGCUAAGUGUUUAGAAACCAAGUGUGUUUUGGAUGGUAAGGUGGAGUCAGCAUUAUAUAUAUUAAUACAUUUUUGGUACCAGAAACAGCAACAAUCCCUUAGUCUGGUGUGUGCAGAUGUAAUAUGUUUCAUGAUAUUUCAGCCUGUAUUUUCUGUCUUAAUAAGUGAAAGCACUGCAGAAUUGGGCUGCAGGCCACUGCCCCAUUUCUCUCCUUUUGUAGUCAGAUCUCCCUUGUGAAUGAUAAACACCCACUCCUUUCAUUUAUUCACCCAUUCACUCAACCUCCUACAAUCUAAGCUGCAUGCUUACCACCUACCUUAAAGAACACCAGUGAUUGCUUAUUGUGACUUACGUCAUAAAUAUGUAUUCUAGACAUGACUUCUCACCUGAAUAUCAGUGUCACAUCCUUCAUAGCCUCAAAACUUUGAGGAAAUAUCCUCUUAUGGCAUACUUUAAAAUUUGUAAUUUUAAAGUAAGCACAAAGUACGUUUUGAGACCUUCAUUUUUUUCUCUAACAAUUCUGUUUUGUUUUUUUUUUUUGUAUUCUGUAUUUUUUGUUAAGUUUAUAUCAGGAUGAUUUGUCAUUAGUGUUCUUGUAACAUAUUUUGGAGUUUUCCUUGUGCAAUGUGGAAAUAGUAAGGUUGACAUUCUGCUUUUAACUCUUCUUUAUAAACUAUGAGGAAUUCCCAAAUAGAAUGUUACCUUGAAAGACUCUUGACAUAAGUAGAACUAAACCAAAUAUUUUAUAUAAUUAUUUUUAUUUUUUAUUUUUGAGAUAGGGUCUUGCUCUGUCACCCAGGCUCAAGUGCAGUGGCGUGAUCAUGGCUCACUGCAGCCUUGACCUCCCAGGCUCGAGCAAUCUGCCCUCCUCAGCCUCUCAGAGUGCUUGGGAUUAAAGGCAUGAGCCACCAUGCUUGGCCUCUGUAAUUCUUAAUUAUUAUUUUAUAUAUGUUAUGAGUAUGAGAACUAAGCAGUUCCAUAAAGAUGAGAAUUAUAAUAUCUCAUUUUAGUAGUAUUUUGCUUUGUAUUAUUUGACAUUUUAUAAAAAUUCAUAGUCUCAAAAAAUAUACAAUGUUCUUCGUCAAGUAGCUAAUACUCUCUUUCUUAGUGUUCGGUUUAACUAUUAAUCUUAUCCUGUUAAAUUAUUUAAAAUUUCCUAAUAAUUGGCACAUAAUAACAGUUUUUAAUGUCAGCAUUGAUAACAUUUUUCUGUCAUAAUAUUCAACUAAGGGAUGCAUCUUCAAUGUAUAAAGCCCAUAAGUAGGUUUUUUCACCCUAGAUUAGAUCUAAAUUGCUUACCUGUUUUUGGAAGUGAAUAUUAUGUUAUUAACAAUAAAUUCCAAACUGCUUUGUAUUACUGACAUUGUAACAAUGUCUUGAUAUGAUGGAGACCCUUGCUAUCACAUUGUCAUUGAUCAUGCACAUUGAUCAUGCCCGUGUUGAAAUAGGCAAUGCCAGAGACAGACCAAAGACGAAACUGGUAGUGAUUUUGGUGAACAUUGUUGCCAUGUUAAACUUGAGUAUAUUUCUUGUUGAACAACCCCAUUUUAGAGAUACGGAAAAUGUUGUGAGGCAGAGAUAUUAAGUAACCCUGCCCAGAGUCGAAUGGUUAAUAAGUCCUUGCCAGGAUUUAAGUGAUAAAACAAAACUCAUGCUUUUAACUACUAUAGUCUUGUAAGCCACUCAACAAGUAUUGGCCAGUUAAACUAAUGAAUUCCCUCAAGGAAUUGAUUCUAGUAAUAGAGAUAAAUAAUCAAGUCAUAAGUCAUGACUCAAUGUGAAAAGUCUUGUGACUAAGGAAUGAACAGUACAAUAAAGGAAACAUGAGGAACAGUGAAUCGUGGUAGGAUUAUGGAGAGGAGGAGGAAGGAAUGGGGGAGAGUGGGGCCUCAGAGAGGUGCACCAAGACUGGGGCCCAGGCCUUGCUUCCAAGGUACCAUGGCGUUCUGUGUUUUUCCUUGUCUUGGGCAUACUAUUCAGUGUUUCGAUUUAUUUACUUGUCCUUACCUCCCACUAGGCUAUAAGCUUUCUGACUGCAGAGGUAAAUUGUGUGUCUUCAUCACUUAGUGCAGGAAGUGGUAGCUAAUGAGUUGGAUAUGUAGGGGCGAGUACAGUGGACAGGUGAAGUCAGGACAUGAUGGACAAAAGCAUGAACAUGAAAGAAGAUGUGAACAUUCGUUGCCUCUUUAGGAAAUGGUCGACAGUGUGGAGUGGACAGAGCACGGACAUGUAGCUUGGGGUAUUGUGAAGGGAUGGGUCAGCCGUGUAUACUUAUCUACCAUGGUAAAAAGUGAUAUUAUUAGAUUUCUGAGUGCUUGCCUUUCCCUAAUGCAUCUUCAUGUCUUUAAGGACAAAGAUGUAGGACCAAGAGUGGGCUACAUCACAGGAGAUGAAAAGAUCUGUUUGCAUAUUUGACCUCUGCUAAUUAUCAGCAGUGUGAUAGUAGGCGUGUCAUCUGACAUCAUCUUGCCUGUUGCAUAGUAGACAUUUGGUAAAGAUUUGUUGAAUGGAUUAAUUAAUAUAAUUAUAUGUUUUUGCGGACUCUGAAGAAUUUGAGAUACAGCUAUAUAAAAGAGUUACUAUUUAUUGGUACAUAUUGCUUAGUAUUUGGAAUAAGCUUGGUAAUUAUUCACUAAGCAGGAAACAGGGUUUAGGGAUUUCCAGGCAUUAGGGACACUGAGCCUUGAGACAGGGUAGCAGCUCUGUGGUUCAGAGUGACUGGUCCACCAGGAACAGAAACAAGCUAGUAUUGGGAGGUGAGGGAGUAACAUUCCUUGGGAGGAUUAUUUGGCAAAACGAAGUAAGAAUCAUAGGGGCAUAGGGUCAUGGAAAAGGCUUCAUUCUUAGUAGAGCUCUGGAGUACCCAUCAAGUCUGGGUGAAGAUGCUUACCUCCCUGAGAGGGCAAGCAUCAGGAAAGCCUGGGUAUGGGGGUCCCGGGCUCCUGAGGCCCAGGACUCAUUGCUAGGAUACAGAUUGCACUGUCAAGUCCAGACUGUCACGUGUGAGUCUAAGCCUAUUGUUUUGGGGCUUGCCAUGGUCUGGAUGGGGCCCCUCUUAAAGGUUAUAGAGUUGUGGAAGAAAGGGACUGACACAUUUUGAUAGUCAAAGAGUAAAAGAAGCUAUGAGUUACCAGUGUGCUGGAUGCUUCUGAAAGCGUUUGACAAGUGCUUUUUGAGUUUUUAAAUUAAAUUACUUUUUUAUUUUUGUCUUCCUCUCUAUAAAUCAUACCAGAGAAGGUAACAUUUUUCUCUAUACUGACUUUGACAAGCCUAGACUAUGCUUUGUCUAUGUCCAGUGUACAAAUGUAGAGAACCCAUUCAUUUCUUUACUCCUCACAUAUUUAGUAAAGUCCGGCUGUGUGCCCUGCCUUUAGGGGACACUGAGCAGAAAGCAGACUCCUCCAGACGAUUGCAUUGCAGUAUAAUUAGCACCAUAACAAGAGUCUGGCAGAUUCUAGUCUGUAGUAGCAAAAUGAAGAGCAAUCAGGUCUAUCCAGGGAAUGAGGAAAUACCUCACAAGAUAGGAAGUGACUGAACUCGGACUUGAAGGAUGAUCAAGAAUCUGCCAGGUGGGUAUGGGGGCCACCUGGCAAAAGGACAGCAUAUGGGAAAGCAGAGGCAUGAAAGACCUUGGUGCAUCCACAAAGCGUUGGGCACGUGAGUCUAGCCAGAUCACAGGUUGUGUGUUGGGGAGCAUUUAGAGAAGAGAACACAAAGUCCUCACGUGCUUUACUCAGGCUUUGGGCUUAAGGAGUGUUUCUGAUGUGGGCUCUGGAGCCAGACUGCAUGGCUGUAAGCCCCGGCCUCUCUGCUUCACACCUCUGUGAUCUUGGACAAGUACCUUAACUUUCUGUUUCUCAGUUUCCUCAUCUCAGAUGAUAAUAGGACAUGCCUCACAGGGUGGUUGUGAGAACCUGAAUAACAUCGUAAAGCACUUCAAACAGUGUCUGGCACAUCAGUUGUUAUUAAUAAUAAUUAUAUAAGAUAAAAUUAUAUAAUUCAUAAUGAUGAUGUUUAAUUUGUAACCUGUAGUCAAAAAGUAGAACCAAAUACAACUUGCAAGGGAACUGGAUGCUUCUGGAAGAGUUUGAUAAGUGUUGUUUGAGUUUAUAAAGUAAAUUACCUUUUUUACUUUCCAGGUAAAAAAAUAUACCUUUGGGAGGGGAACAACACACACUGGAGCCUGUCGGGGGGCGGGGCCACAGGAGGGAGAGCAUCAGGAUAAAUAGCUAAUGCAUGUGGUGCUUAAUACCUCAGUGAUGGGUUGAUGGAUGCAGCAAUCCACCACGCACACAUUUCCCUGUGUAACAAACCUGCACGGCAUGCACAUGUAUCCCGGAACUUAAGAAAAAAAAAUACAUUUUUUCUUUCCAGGACAGCGUCAGUCCUUAAGAGGCUAGCUCAAAGACUAGAGGAAAAAUAGACUACUAAAUAAAUCAAAAUUAUUUAGUAGGGUAUAGAGUUAUCCAUAAAGUGCUGGGGGUCACUAAUUAUUAAAGCAGAUAGAGCACAGGUAGUUGUUGAGCGUAGAACAGCCCAAUCAGAAUGAUGCCUCAGAAAGGCAGUAGUUGGCCUCCCAGAGUGGAGCAUGGAUUGCAGCAGGGGGCUGAGGCUGGAGGGGGAGAAGUGUUGAACUAAUUCAAGGGAUGUUGGAGGGCUAAACCAGUGUCUCUUCUGCUAAAUCUGAGCAGAAGAGACAGAUCUGGAAGCUUCUGGUAAGGUAGGCUUGAUUGAGUUUGGUGAGAAGUUAGAUGAGGAGGGUGAGAACCUAGCAUCUGGGUGUCUGCUAGAUAGAUGCUGCUGCACCACACCAAUGUCCGUGUGUCUGGGUACCGAGGUGGUGUUCAGGACAGGUCUUCUCCACGUACUGCCGCUGAGCUCACAUCCACGCUGUGCAUGCUGGGCUGAGUUCUCUUCAGGCUGUUUUCAGCUGACUUAAAUGCAACACGUGAUGAUGAGCAUAUUUACAUAAUGUAUGCCUGGUGAAAUCACGAAAGAUUGGAAUUUCCCAUUUUAAUUCCAUUUUAAAGAUGCUUGUUAAGCAAAAGGAUAUAAUUCAUUUUUCAAACUGCUGAAAUGUUAUUUGGCCUCUUGAAUCAAAGGCAUUCCGCAAGUGUUUUCUUUAUUACAUGCCUUAAACUUUAAUUAGAAUUUAAUUAUAAGAUCCUGAAGGCAUGAGCAAGAGGAGCAGAUGGGAUAGUAAAAGCAGCUUAGUGAGGGAGGAUUAAAGAUUAAAAGUUGCUUGUUAAUGGCAUAAGAAAUGAACAGAGAGCUAAAUUACUAUGCUUUUGUGCUAUCCUGAUGCUUUUUCGAUUCUGUAACUUAUUCCUGGUUGCAGGUUUUUCAAUUCUGCAACUUAUUCCUGGUUGGAAGUUGAAGAAUCUCACAAAUUAGAUUUUUAAUUUUUUGAGUUGCUAGAGUAGAUUUGUACAUAGAAAACAGGUAAAACCUGACAAAAAGGUGUUUUAUGGCUAGUAGCACCUUGUACAAUAAUUUCUGCAUUGUAGGGGCUUAGUGGUAUUUACUGAAUUGAACUAAAACUUACAUCAUCUCACUAGUAAACAUCGAAUGAGCAUAAAAUAAGAUUUUUUUUUAGAGAUGGAUGGGGAAGGUGUGAGUCUAUAAGUCCAGGCUAACCUGUCCCAUGGAAUGUUAGAUACCUACUCAGGAAGGUAACUUGUAUGAACCUCCCACCUUUAGCCUACCCCCCAGUCGACCUUAGUCAUUUGCCCCACUUGGUUGGUUGGCUAGAGGAGUGGUAGAAAUUUGGUGUGGGAAACACUUUGAGACUGCUCCUCAUGUCACACAGUGAGGAUGACCUGCUCUGCUCUCUGGUGCUAUGUUACGAUGAUCUCCCGUUAGGCUAAAUUAUUCUACUUCUUAGUGCUUUUUCCCCUAGCUUUUUUUUUUUUCUUUUUGAAAUCUGAUAUUUAGAGUCCUCUUCCCCACUUAAUUGCAAGCUCAAUGAAGAAAAACUAGAGAACAAUAAGAUAGAAAAGAAGACAAAAAUGUAGUGAAACAAAAAGCAUUCUAUCUCCUAUUUUCCAGGAACAAAUGUUUUUUAAAAAGCUUUUUUAAGCCUGUUAAUAGACAGUUGAUUCUUCAUUAUUUGCAGAUUCUUUGUUUGCAAAUUUGCCUACUUACUAAAUCUUAUUUGUAACCCUCAAAUCAAUACUUGUGGCACUUUCACAGUCAUUCGCAGAAAUGCUCAGAGAGGAGGAUAAUUUCUGAGUCUCUCGUCAUGCGUGUUCCUAGCCGAUGGCAAAUAACACAACACCCUGCCUUCUUGUUUCAGCUCUCAUAGUGUAAACAAGUGUCCUUUUCGAAGUCUACUCGUGCCAUGUUUUUCUCAUUUUUGUGCUUUUUGUUGGCGAUUUCACCAUUUAAAAUGCACCCCAAGCAUUGUGCAAAAGUACUGUGUAGUGUUCAAGUACAGUGCAAGAAAGCUGCGAUGUGCCUUACAGAGACAAUAACGUGUGUUUGAUAAGCUUCAUUCAGGCAGGAGUUAAGUGCUGUUGGCUGUAAGUUCAGUGUUAUUGACUCAACAAUAUAUAUUAAAUGAGUUGUUUUUAAGCAAGAAUACACAUGAAACAGGGUUGCGUAUUGAUGAGUUGGCAAAAAUAUAACUGGAGGCUCAGAGGAACCUAGCCCUGUAUUUCCCUUAGGAACAAUGGUCCAGUGUUCCCUAAUUUAAUGUUUUUGGAGACUACCAAAAAUAAUAAGGUCAGCCAUGUAUCUUUCUCCUUUUCUCCUUGCUCUUGCUUGAUCUUUCCAUCUCUUGUUACCUCAAUCUGUGUGUAUAUGAUAUGCAUAUAUUUACUUAAAUUAUAUAUGCAUAUAUUUAGCAAUUAUGAUAUCACAUGAUACACGAUUCUGCAACCUGUCUUUUAACUUAUCAAUUGUGUUGGCCUUUGGGCUGUUUGCACUGAGAUCCAUUUGUCACCCUUGCCCUGCUCUGCAAGGGUGCUGUGUUACAGGGGGUUGACCCCUGCCCCCUGACAAUUUGUCAUCAGUGGGAGAUGGCAAGGCAAGAGAAAGAGAAGCUGGAGUAUUUGUCCCUCCCUCUGUCUGCCUUGGGCAGCAUCUCUGGCAGUGGCCCCUCUACAGCUAUCCCACCUGCAGGUUGGGUCCUCCAUGGCUCUGUCAUCGGCUGGUUGGUCCUGGGUCUCGAGCUUUAGCCCUGCCUUCUUCCUUUGUCCUUUUAGCUGAUGGGUGGAAGAAGCUUCCUGCUGAUGCUGAUCUCUGAGUUUCUUCCCUGUCCCCUGGGUAGAGCAUCAGAUUUAAAAGCCAAGGCAAGACAAAAAAUGAGAGAAUGGUAGCAAAGAUCCAACACUUUACAAGACCGCCUGAGAAAAGGGAGGAGGGGGUGGUUCGACACCAGGGCCUGCACACUGAGUGUGUGAUGUUGCAGCUCUGCAGGCACAGAUUAAGCAGCUAAGAUGCCAUCAAUGCUUGGAAAGCAGCCGGUGCCUCUUGUCCUGAGCUUAUUUGUCUGGAAUAUGAUUCCCUUGAACCUGACUAGCUCAUCCACGGGGAGAGAGAAAAAAAAAUAUUCUGAUAGUUAUCCUGACCAGGCUCUAACAGGGCCUCCUUCCCUAGGAUAUAAUUUUUUCUGGCCUCUUUCCAUUCACUUCUUCACAUUAGGACCCUUUUCCCCCAGAGUGUGAGAUUCCCUGAGGGCUCUAAAAACUGGAAUGCUAUACAGCAUUUUAAGCCCCCUGUGUUGGCACAGUCCUUAUUAAAAAUGUAUUUUCCUCAAGCCAUGGCUGCACCCCCUGAAGUGUGGAUUAACAGAAAGGCCUUCAGAGCUGGAAGACAUUUUUGAAGAACCGCUGUACCAAGUGGCAUUAAAUAUUUAUUGCCUACUACAUGUAAAUUGUUCAUCAUCUUGUUUUAACUCUUGGACCAAAAGGUUUCUCAUCUGCUUUCUGCUAAAGUGGAAAUCACAGGAAAGGUACUCUUUACUUUGCUGUGGUAUUUUGUUUUCCCAGGAAUACGGAAUAUUUCUUUGUUCUCAUAAGUAAUACUAGAAAAGAUUGCCUUGACUCUCAGCAUUUCAUUGGGAGGCCAUGUGGUGUCAUGAUGGAGAAAAACUCGAAUUCUGGGGCAAGUGCAUUGGGCUUUGCCACCUGCAAGCUGUGUUGGCUUGAGAACCUGAUACCAUUUAUGUUUGUUGUGCUGGAAAAAUGGGACAUUGCAUAAAUAGCAGAUAGCACAAUUCCUGGCACCCAGUAAGUUCUCUCUUUCUCCUAGGUCUUCUAUUUGGGACUUUGCAAAUACAUUUCUAAGCAACCUAGAAUAAAAUAUGCUAUUAAUAUGCUGUUAAUAAUAACCAAAAGCACUCAGCUUAAUCUUUACUUAUUAAAUAAAACUGAAAUGUUGCUCAGACACCUUUUGCUGUUUUUGGAAUGCCUUUGUAGACACUUUUGAUCUUGCUUAAAAAACAUAACAGCAUUUCAAAGGCUUAUCUUAGCUAUUCUUAUUCAUACCUGAAAACCUACAGAGUUUGGAUAAUUUUGGCACACAUAUGUGUGCACGCAUGUAUAUGUAUAAAUAUUCUGUCUCUCUAAAUAUAUAUGUAUAUGCAGGCACAUGUAUAACUCUUUAAGAAAUGUUUUUCUAAUGUUUAAUUUUCUUAAAGUCUGUACUUCACAUCAUUUUUUUCCCCAGAACUGUUUAUCCUCACUCCAGACAUGACCCUUGGAAAGGUGGCAGAAAAAACAAACGGCUGGUGUGUUUUGGGGCAGUCUGCAUUCCUUUUAACUCUCUGAGACCAGGCUUAUGCAUGGGCUUUCAAGCUAUUUGUCCAGAGGCCCAACCACUUUGAUUUCUGCUUGAAAAUUAGCCUGUUGUUCAAGCUCAGGAGAGCUUCCACAGAGCUUUCUUGGGUUCGCGAACUAGAGAUCUAUGAAGUGUUUGCUUUUAUUUGUAACUUUAACCACGGCAGCCUUAACUGGACUUUUGUUUUCUUAUUUAACUUUUAUCCAUGUAACCUUAACCUAAGUUCUUUUUCAAAUCUCCAUCCUCCCCCAUCUCACAAUUUCUAAUCCCUCUUUUGUCCUUAGAUUUUUCCUUCAAAGUCAGGAUAUGACAUUUAUAUCUAUGCUUUAGGAAGUAUCUGAAAGCUAACAUACACAUAGAAUUAUGAUUUUUUUCUUGGGUUGCUUAGGAGGAUUAAACAAAGGUUUUAGAAGGCAGAAUUCAGAAAAAAAUUGAUAGAAGUUGUGCUGCAGCUUGGAGGGGAGUGUGGAUUUUAGAAAGCAUAAGGACACUUUCAUUUGUCCCUUUCAUAUGGACUUUUAUUUCCUCUGCGAGAGGCCCAGGGGCCUGGCCUGUGGAUGGUUUAGACAGGAAAAGACUGAAGGGAUAACUGCUUCCAGACCUUCAGCCUUGAAUGUUCAGCCAUUAUUCAAGCCGUUGAGAAAGGGAGCAAGAGGCAUAAGGAGGCUUCGGGAGUUUCCAUGCAGCUUCUCUGAGUUCCAGCUUGUGUGCAUUGUUCUCCAAAUGUGUCCCCAGCACUACUGAAAGGACUUUCAUACCUCAACUAACCCUUAUUGCAAGCCUGUGAAGGAAGAGUUUUUUAUAUAUAUAUAUAUAUAUAUAUAUAAACAGACAAGGCAACUAAAGCUCUGGGAGGUUACAGAAACUUAAGGCCUAAGUAGGGUUACAUUGAGACCAGAUUAAUCAGUUAGUAGAUUGUCUUUCUAUUUCAUCAUGUGCUUCAUUUCCUCCUUGGUUUACAUGACCCUUCUUUGGAAAUUUCCUUCUGGUAAUAUCUUAGUUAAAUGAAAUAACUAAGUUUUAUGGAGUAUCCAUUAUGUGUUAGGCAUUGUUUUAUGCAAUAUGCAUCUAUGUAGUGCACAUUCUGAUAGGAACCAUGUGAAGAAGGUGUAUUACCUCCAUUUUAGACAGGAAAUCCCUGCAAUACAGAGGGUUAGGUAAUUUGCUCAAGAUCACACAGGACACAGUAGGUGACACCAGGAUUUGAGCCCAGGUCUGAUUCCAGAACUUAUGCCAUGCCCACUACACCAGCCGUCCUUAUUAAGAGGAAGGCCAUUGGUAUGAGGCCACUUGAAAUAGACAUGGUAGAUAUGUGGCAAUCAAUGCAAAGGUAUUGUCUUUCAUGCUCUGUUGCAAUCUCAUUUCAUUUCUAGCAUUAUAGGUAUUUAAAGCAGAGGUAGGCUUGCUUUCUUAGUUUCAGUUUUCUGAGAAACAAAGAUAGUAACAACAAUGAUGAUGGAUCUUGUUACCAUAUGUGAAUAUCUGUGUGUACUAGGCACGGUACUUGGUCUUUACACAUGUUCUUCUAGGUUAACCUUAUGACAACUCUGUGAAGUUUUCUCAAAUUUAUAUCUGAGAAAGCACUCAGAAAGGUUGAGUCACUUGCUUGCCCACAUCACACUACUAGUAAGUGGAGGAGUGAGGAUUUGAACCUAAGACCUCUUACAAUAAAAUUAUGUUCUUUCCACUCAGUAUAUGGGACAUGUAUCCCUGGGGGCACAUGUGAGAACUAUAAUUGGUCUGUAAGAUUAUUGAUGAUGGUAUAGGGAUAGGGUGUUAAAGAACAUUGAUGCCCAUAGUGAAAAAGUAAUUCCCUUUCACUUGUCCUACCAACCAUCUGGUUACAUGAAAGAGGAAGUCUCAGUUAGGUGCCAGUAUGCCUUUUACAAUUCUAACAGAGAACAGGGCUCAGACUCUGAGGCUCGGGCAGGUAAUUGAAUCUAGAAGACCAUGGUGACGUUCUUUUUGUUUUUAUUGUAUUUUAAUAUCUUCUCAUUAAAAAAUAUUAUAAUGUGUUCAUAUAUACAAAAUAAAUGUAAUGUAUAUAUAAGGUUAAAAGAAUAAUAUAAUGAGUAUCCAUGUACCUAUCACCUAUUGAAGCAUUAGAUUAAUUUUAGUUACUAUGGGAACCUUCUGUGUCACUCUUCCCAUCCCAACUUCUUUCUUUCUCUCCUACCAACAUCUUACAUAAUCACUGUAUAACUAUCAAAAUCAGCCAGUUAACAUUCACAUAAUACUAUUACUCAGUCUACAGACUUUUUGCUAGUUUUGCCAGUUGUCAUACUGUUUCAUUUCCUGGACCAGAAUCUAGGAUCACACAAUACAUUUACUAGUCAUAUCUCCUUUGUCUUUGGAAUAGUUCCUCACUCUUUUUGUCUUUCAUGACCAUGACGUUUUUGGAGUCUGGUUAGGCAUUUUGUAGAAUGUCCCUCACUUUGGGUUGGUCUGAUGUUUCCACAAUAUUAAAUUCAAAUUAUGUGUUUUUGGCAGGGAAGCUACAGAAAUGAUGUUGUGCCUUUCACAGUGCAUCACAGCAGGAGGCACAUGAUGCCGAUUUAUCGUAUCACAGGUGAUGUGAACUUUGGCCAAUUUGUUAAGGUUGUGUCUUCCAGUUUAUCCACUGUAAAGUUACUAUUUUUCCAUUUGUAAUUAAUGAUUACCUUGUAGGGAGAUACUUUGAGAUUAUGUAUAAUAUCAUGCUUCUUAUACCUUUGUCCACUAAUUUUAGCAACUAUUGUAAAUUCUUGCCUGAAACAAUUAUUCCUGUGGUUUUUCCAUAUGGUGUUUUUCUAUGAUUAUAAUUCUUUCUAUAUUUAUUAACUGGAAUGCUUUGUAGGUGGCUUUAUCCUCGCCACACACUUAUUUAUUCAUUCAGUUGUUUAUUUGUAUCAGUAUGUACUUACAAAUUCUUAUUUUAUUGUCUGGAUUAUAAUCCAUUAGUAUCAUUAUUUUGUUUUGCAAAUAGUCCUUUUAACCAAUGGGGAUCCCUUCAAAUUAGCUUUUCUAUCUUUCUGACAUGUCUCCAUCUUUUUUAAGGCAUUUUUGCUUUCUGGUGCCAGAAGAUACCACUUUGUGCUUUACUUGCUCCAACCCUGAGAGAAGCCUCCUCUUGCUGUUCUGCAUCCAUUCCUCUCAGUCACUCCUUCAUGCACUAUAAUAUGAUUUCCACUCUCCCCAGUGCACUGACACUUCCGUCACUUAGGUCAUUGCUAAAGCAGUAGAUAUUUUAAUUCUUCUAUUACUGCAUAUCAGACAUCUCUUGGCCCCAUAUCAGAUCUUCUCAGGAGGACAGUAAAGGGAAAUUGUACCAUCUCUUGUUCCAGCUGCCGUGACCAAGUUUGCAUAGACUCUGAAAAACUUCCUACAGUAUAAGCUGACAGUACCUCACCUCAUGCUGCAUGCUUUUCCAUAGGGCACCCCACGAGGUUCCAUGGGGUUUCCUUGUGGUUGCUACCUCUGGAUCUCACUCUGUUCCCACACAUGUACAACCUGGAUAGAGAAUUAAUGCCUCCUUUCUCUCUAUCGUGGAUGGUUCUGAGAUACAGUUCAUGUGGCUUGGGGUGUGGAGAGGUUGAGGAUGAUCCUAUGGGAUAGAGAACGAGUCACUUCUAGUGGGGCCAUCUUGAUACCACAACUUCAUCUUGCCUCCCCCUCCUUAUUAUUUGUUUUAUUCCCUUUGUCUAUCAGUCCUCUCCUUCUCCCUAAGAUUGCACUACCUGAUGCAGUAGAACCCUCUUCCUUGGGUCUGCUGUCUCGGGGACCCAGGAAAAGAUGUGCAGUGUUUAAACUCCUUCUCUAUAAUCUCUUAACUUUCACACUAUCACAUUUUCAUUCAUUUAUUCCAAUUCAUUCAUUCAUUUACACCUUAUUUAUUGAGACUUUCCCUGUGUGAGACAUUGUGUACAGGUAGACAAAAAUCUUGAUCUUAUAGAAGUUAUUGUAUUUGGGGGAGCAGAAAUAACUAAAUAAAACCAAUUCAGCUGAAUUAUAAGUGCUUUUAAGAAAAUGCAACAGGGAGAGGGCAGAGAGUGGGCCACGUGGGGCCUGGCAUUGGGAUGGUUACCACAUACACUCUGAGGAAAUGACAUUUGAACUGAUAAGGGGUCAGCAAGAAGAAAUGGGCUGAGAGAAGACUGAUCUAUUCACAGGAAAGAGGAAGUGCAAGAGCCCUCAUUUUCUGUUUUGCACUAGAACUGCUUUCCUAUGAUUCUUCAGAUUGUGCCACCUUUCUUCCAACUCCCAUGCAUUUGCACAGAUUGUUUCUUUGACCUGGAAUGCCCUCUCUGACUUACCAAGCUGGCAGAUUUCUAUCCUUAGCUCAGAUCUCAUCUAAAGCAGCUCUCCACCCCCAGGGACAUUUUAAGUCCUUUUUCUGUUGUUGGUGUGCUGUGCUUUGAGCACAGUAUUCAUUUAUAAUAGUGAUGUCAGUGUACGCCUUAGAAUUGUUCACCUGCAUCUCUCCUUCUUGGACUAGGAGCACUCUGAGGGCAGGACUAUGUUUGUUUACUUUGUAUUCCCAACAAAGUGCUUAUAGGGAUUUAAAUCUAUUUAUUGAUGAGUUGGAUGGAUGAAUGGAUGAGUACAUGGGAGAAAGAGGAAAAAUGAUAUAUGAAUUGAAAUAAAUAAAUGAAAGAGCCAGUGAAUAAAUGACAGUGACCUGACCUUAAGGCGUUGUCUUGUUUGUGGGUGAGACAGGAGUAUAACCAUUCAGAGUACUGUGAUGAAUGCUUAGAGAUUCUCAGUGCAUGAAUAACAGUGGCAGUCAGCAAGUUCUGCUCAUAGAUGCAUAUUGUUUCAGCUAUUUCAUGCUUAUUUAUUUAGUUUUUAAGAAAUUCAUUUAGGUACCAAACAUAAAAAAAAACCCAGACUUGCAGCUUUCCAGAUUUGGGGCCAGACACAUGACUGUAAUCCCAGCACUUUGAGGGGCCGAGGUGUGCGGAUUGCUUGAGGCUAGGAGUUUGAGAGCAGCCUGGGCAACAUGGCAAAACCCCGUCUCUACAAAAAAUACAAUAAUUAGCUGGGCGUGGUGGCACAUGCCUGUAGUCCCAUCUCCUUGGGAGGCUGAGGCAUGAGAAUUGCUUGAACCUGGGAUGUGGAAGUUGUAGCAAGCCGAGAUUGCACCACUGUGCUCCAGCCUGGGCAAUAGAGUGAGAUUUCAUCUCAAAAAAACCCAAAAAACAGAUUUGGCAGUGCUGGACCCUUCUACAUGGAGCUGGGGACAAAAAUCUGCUGGAAAGUAGGAAAUUAUUAGAAUAACUAACUGUAUUAAAAUAUGUUGAAUUCUUCUUGUCAUGACUGUUUUGACAUUUGUUUGUACUAGUUAAGGGAAAAUGAAACUUCAGGUUGACAGCCUUUACCUUCCUUGUGCCAUAAUUAAUUUGCUCUAUUCUGUUUGUUCAGGAAAUUCAGCUUUUGAAGGCCCAGAAAGAGGACUAAGGGUGCAGGUGGCAAGGAAAGGUUGAUUUGUGGUGACCUGGCAUACUGUAUUCCAUCUUUAAGUCCUCACCACAAGUAGGCCUUUAUCCAGGUUCUUGUUACCUGGAAAUGUGUGUUCAUUUGGGGUAUCUAGAUGAGGCAGGACUUCAAGGAAGGGGAUGGAUAAUGCACUUAAUCUUCAUCUUCACAUAAGGAUAGCUGCUCUUUAUCUUCUCCCUCUGGAAGCUGCCAUUGUGAGGCAGCAUUAAGGUGGGAGAGGACCCUCUGGAGUUCAUCCAGAACCCUCUGGGGGCACCUGUGUCCCUUCUGUUUGUCAGUGUAUCAGCCAUGGAUCCUGCGUGAAACAGGUGGCACAUUUAAAUGGGGUAAUCCGAGAAGAGUGGACAAGUGUAGGGAAACCACAUGGAUAGUGCAAGAUGCUUGGCUAUCUAAAGUGGGGCUGGUACUCUCUCUGGGCCUAAGGAACAAGGAGAGGGGCUACGAGCAGGCCCUGGGGAGAUUGUUUUGUGGAGGUACUUACCUUUGUGACCUUUGGUGGAGAGCUGCAGCCAUCCUACACUUUCUCCUAGUCCACUGAUAUCCCUCUGUGUCCUCCAUUAGCUGAACCUGGCUGGAGGCCAGAGGCAGAAGAGCCCUCUGGUGUGCUCCACACCCAUCAGCAUCCUGGCUUACAAGGCAGGGUGGAGAAAGUUAGAGAUUGAAUUUGAAGAGCACAUGGAAGAUGUCUGGGACAUCUGGGCAUUCUUUCUGUGUGGUUGGUUCUUGUGGUCAGAUAUUUGUGGAGGAGUGAGGUGGUGGUGGUAGUGGCUGUGCUUUAGAGUCAGUGAGUCUGGGACAGGAUCACAUCUGCCCCACUCGCUAACGGAGUUACCCUCAGCUCAAGGUCAGCAGGCACCGAUUUCUUUGCCGUCUGGUGGGGCCAAGGGCAAAUGCCUAUCUCAAAAAGCUUUGGGAAGAUCAAAAAUGAAAAUACUUAAGUGUUUUUUUGCAGAUUUGGAAAAGGCUGAAAGAAGUUUUAUUAAAAUGUGAGCAAUAUACCUCAAUAAAGUUGUUUUCCUAUAUAAGACAAAUAAAACUGUGUUGUGAUUUCACAACAAGUGUUGAUUUUUUUCUUCAUUAUAUUUUUCUGUAUUCCAGAUUUUCUGUCAUCAGAAAACCAGACAUCCAUAAGUGCUAUUUAGAAAUAUGUUAGUACUGCCUUCAAAUUAUUACUGUUGGCUAAUAUUGCCUUCUCUGGGUUACUGAGGUAUGUGAAUUCACAGCUGCAGCAUAGCUGACUUGACUAUGGACAGACUAGAGUGAACGUGUAUGUCAUUUCUUACGAUGUGCCCAUGGAUUCAGGUCUAGUGCCCCAUCCCCAGGAAGCCUUUGGCCCUUCAGAUGCUUCUCCUCUGAGCUCCUGCAGCUCCUGGGCUGCCCCUAGCAGUUAUCACACUGUUUUGCGGUUUUCUCCACCACUAGACUGUGGUCUCCUCUAGGUCCAGGACUGAAUUUUAUUCAUCUCCAGGUCAGUGUCUAGCAUUGUCUUGUAAAUGCUGUCUUUAUUCAUGUUGCCCAGCUUCUACCACACGGCUACUGGAAGUUCUCAAGCUCAUAACACCGUAGCUUCUACAACAGAGAGCAACUGACUGUGCUUUCUCCUUUCUGUUUUCAAAGCCCUGGGAAAGAAUUCUGAUUAGUUUCAUUUGGGUCAAGUGUACCUACAUCCCUUAUUGAACCAACUAUACCCAUGGAGAGGUAUAUUACAGUGAUCUCAGCUUUGGUCAAGUGCUCAUUCCCAGAGGAAUCUGUUGUGUGGCCAAUAGGGUAGGAUCUGUACAACUAUGACAGGUCUUAUUUAAAUCAAUUAGUUACAGUGGAGAAGAGAAUGAAUCAGUUAGGAAUGCUUUCAGCUGCAGUGACAAUGCAAAAAAGCUUUUAUUUAAAUCAGUUAGUUGCAGUGGGGAAGAAGCAUGUAUCAGGAAUGCAUUUGCAAGGGAGCAAAAAUUGGUUCUUGGGGGAUGAAAAAGAUCUUAGAUAUUACAAUCAUUUGUGGCCUUCUAAAGCCCAUCCUUAUGUAACAGCAUAAGUAGAUACACAAUCUGUCUGUGGUAUUGAAAUUUCACAGUGGCAGGGAAAAGGAAAAGACUGUCUGGAAAGGGUCUUUAGUGGGGGCGAUAGUGAAAAAAAAGUUUGAGAGUGAUUUAUGAUGACAAUAAUCAUACCUAACUUAUUUAGUAGUUAUGCACCAGGAACUGUUAUGAAUGCCUUACAUAUACUAUAUUAAAUCAUUUCACCAUAUAUCCAUUUGACAGUGACCAAAACACAAAUAGUCUUGAUUUCCCACUCUCACACCCCUAAAUUACAAGUACAAAGAUGAUUUGACCAUGUCACCUUCAGCAUAUCUUUAAUUCUUUGGACUUUUCCCUCAUGCUAGCUGCCUCAUGGUUGUAGGAUAGUUGCUGCAUCUCUGGACGUUACAUUCUCCUUUGAUGCUGGAAGAAUUGGUGAGAAGAGCAUGAUGAGAUUUUUUGUUUUGUUUUUUAAAUGAGAGGAGCAAAACCUUUCCCAGGAAUCUUCUCUUCCUACUAUACUUCUGCUUAGGUCUUAUUGGCUGGAAUUAAGUCCCAUGGCCACUCUUAGCAGCAAGAAGCAGGGAAAGUGGAAAACAAGAUUAUCAUGGUUGGCUUAAACCUGCACAUUCCAAUAUGAUAGUUACUAGCUAUAUGGCUAUUUAAAUUUUUUUAGAGAGAUAUAAUUCAUAUACCCUAAAAUUCACCAUUUUAUGUAUACAGUAUAGUAUUUCUAGUAUAUUCACAGGAUUAUGCAACCAUACCCCAGUAUCCGAUUCCAAAACAUUUUCUUCGCCCUCAAAAGAAAUCUCAUAUCCGUAGCAGUAAGUCCUCAUAUCCCUCUACACCUAGCCAUUGGCAACCACUAGCCUACUUUCUUUCUCUAUGGAUUUUCCUGGACAUUUUGUUUGGCUUCUUUCACUUGGCAUAAUUUUUUCAGGGUUCAUCUAUGUUGUAGUAUGUGCCAGUAAUUUUUUUAUCAGUUCCUGUUUUAAUUGAUAAUACUCUGUUGCAUGGAUGUAUCCUAUUUUGUUUAUCCAUUCAUCUGUUGAUGGACAUUUAGAUUGUUUCACUUUUUAGUUACUGUGACUAAUGCUGCUGUGAACACUGAUUGAUGUACAAGUUUUUAUAUCAACAUAGUUUUGAUUUUUCUUUGAAUUCUCUUGAGCCUAUUAGAAGGAGUGGAAUUGUUGGGUUUUAUGGUAACACCAUGUUUAACCCUUUGAGGAAAUGUCAAACUGUUUUCCAAAGUGGCUACACAUUUUGUACAUCCUGGUAGGAACAUGUAAGGAUUCCAAUUUCUCCACAUCCUUGUGAGCACUUGUUAUUUUUUGUUUGUUUUUAUUAUAACCAUCUUAGUGGGUGUGAAGUGGUAUCUCAUUGUGGUUUUGGUUUGCCUUUAUGUAAUGACUACUAAUGUUGAGAAUAUUUAAUGUGCCUAUUUUCCAUUUGUAUAUAUUCUUUGCAGAAAUGUCUGUUCAGAUCAUAUGCCCAUUAUAAAAUUGGAUUGUCUUUUUAUUGUUGAAUUAUAAUAGGUACUUAAAUUUAAAUUAAUUAACUUUAAGUAAAAUAGAAAACUUAGUUCCUCAGUCAUACUGGCCACAUUUCAAGUGCUCAGUUGCUGUGUGUGGAUAGUGGCUAUGUUAUUGGACAGUUGCAGAUAAAGAUAAUUUACAUGAUUGCAGAAACUUCUGUUGGACAGCACUGGCUUAGAACCACCAUGAUUGAUCACUUAUAGCUGGGCAUAUGACUUCUCUAAAUAAAAUUGAGGUUUUGUUAAGCUAAGGAAGGAUUGGUACUCCAGAAAGAGUGAGGUGUCCUGGUCCCAGAAAAGGAGGUUAUGCAGACUCAGUGUAUAACUCCUAAAGAUGCAUCAGAGUUUACCAAGGGAAGAACUGGGGCAGGGGUUGAGUGGGAGGGCAAAAUUCUAGACCAGGGCUUGGCAGAUGUCUUUUGCAAAGGGUCAGAUAGUAAAUAUUUUGGCUUUGCUGACUAUAUGAUAUCUGUUUCAACUAUUGAACUGUAACCAAAAAGUGUCUGAGACAGAUUUCAAUCGAUUUAGAGAGGUUUAUUUUGCCAAGGUUGAGGAAGCACCCGAGAAAAUAAACACAAGUUACGUUAGGAUCUGUGACUGGUGUUUUGUCCAAAGAGGAUUGUGAGGACUUCAGGAUUUAAAAGGGAAAGAGUGAGCAGGAAGGGAAGGAGGAAAGAAAAAAAAAAGUUUGAGGGGCAUAGGCGAUGAGGCAAGUGGUUACAUUCUUGUGAGGCUUUGAUUAGUGCUCACCAAAUCCACAGUUUACAUGUGAAAAGAGGAGUGGGGGAAAGUCAUUUAUGCUCAGUAAAUCUACAUUUUACGUAAGAUAAAGGAAGCAUGUGAAGUUACAGCAACCCAUUUGAGAACAAAAGGAUGGCAGUUUUUUGAUUUUUUCUUUUUUUGUGUGUGUGUGUGUGACUCAGUUCCCAAGCUUAACUUUUCUCUUUAACAUAGUGAGUUUGGGGUCCAAAGAUUUUAUUUUCCUUUCACACAACUUUGUCCUUAUAGUGAAAAAGCAGCCUAAGACAGGCCAUAAAUGAAUGGACAUGGCUGUGUUCUAAUGGAACUUUAUUUACAAAAACUGGCAGCAGGCACAUUUGGGCUACAGGCCAGGGUUUCCUAGGGACAAUACAUAGAAAAGUAUGGAAGCCAGAAGGGGCCUGGCAUACUGAAAUAAAGAGAAUGGUAAGACGUUUGGUAUGGCUGAAAACUGGCUGUAGGAGCUAUGGCUGUAGAGAAGGCUAGGAAUAGAGACUGGAACCAGAUUAUAAAGGGUCCGCAAUGCAUAUCAAUGUUGUUUUGUUCUGGUUGGUGGUGGUGGUUGUGGUGCUAGUGGCAGUGGUGGUUUUCUAAAAUCCUCUAAGUGGCAAGAAGCCGUCAAAUAUUUUUAAGUAGGACAUUAUAUGAUUAUGGCUUUUUAGACAACCCUCUGGCAGCAUUGUGAAAAGAAUAUUGGAGGAAAUGAGGCUAGAGGUAAAAAAAUACCAGUUAAGCUUUGUAUUUUGUAUUAAAAUAAAGAUCUGGUAAUUAUCUUGCUAAUUGCAUCAGUAGAGACAUAGACCACCAAGCUGAUAAUUCUUAUCCUGACUAACCUACUCACUAUGAGCUGAGUAAAAAGCAGUAUUGAUUUAAAUGAGUUAUGAAGAGUGGGGCUUGGAUAUGCUCUUUUUAUAUCCCAGGGGAAUCACCCUGGAAACCUAGAGAACUGGUUCCAAGUAUUCAUCUGAGAACAUCUGUGACUCUCAGAAAGUUAUGAGAUUGGAGUUGUACGGGGAAACUCGCUGUGGCCUUGGAAGAGUUGACUUCUAAAUGGGGUAGUGAACUUAUUCUCCGUGGCUCAGUUCUAAAAGGCCCUAAGAGGAGAAAAGGAUUCUUGAUGAACUACUAAUUGAUGAUUUUAGGUCCAGAGUUAAGCAUAAUAUGGAGGUUUGCCUGAGAGUGUCUGCCGUCAGUGAAGAUGAAUUAUCCAUGUGGGCUUAGAAAAUCACACAUGCAAAUUAUGUGUCAAUGGAUUUUUUUUUCAACAUGCUAAUCCUAGCCUUUGAGUACACAGCAUAUUUUCAAAGCCAAUUUUGCAAACAACUCUAUGGUAAAUGCUGCUAAGCUGUUGAUAAGUUGGCUUUCCAUUUGUAAGCCUAUUAGUUCAGAAUCUUCUGAAGUUUAAUUCAAAAUGAGAUAAUGUGUAGUGAUUUGACAGUUUUCAUUCUGUGACGAUGCUCUUCAAGAAAGCAUCUUGGCUUGUUCACUAGUUGAAUCCUCACCAGUUCCUGAAAUUAUGAAAUGUAAAUUUGUUAUAAGCAGCCGCUUUGGGCCCUUCACAAGGCAGAAUUGUACCUUAUCCCUGAGUGGAAAUAAAUGAACAUCUCAUGUGUGUAGCUUCUCUCUCUCUGUACAUCCUGACUCCAAAUGCUGUGAGGCACCAGAAAAUGUCUCCUGAAUCUGAUUUUGGGUGGCUGGAUCAAUGUCCAGAGGGAAUUAGGAAUUUUUCCAAUGGUGGUACAGAUAGAGGUGAUAACAUUAGAAAAGACUGACCCUUGACAAGACCCACAUUAGUGAAGUCGUUAUUCCCAAGGAGUUGGGUAUGUACUUCCCACGUGUUGUGAAAACAGGGCUCUAUUACCUUGCCAGCAAUACCCCAAAGGCAGAGGCUGUAUUUGUCCUUGGAUCUCAGUCUUUGACAUUGUUUUGGGAAGGUAUGAUGAGAGGCAUGAGGAAACCUCAUCCAUUUUGUGAGUCCAGUGUACUUAAACGGUAGAGACUGACUCCAGGGCAUUUGGAGUUCACAGAAUUUGUCAAAUUAUUUUUCAAGCUUGUAGGGUUCAAGACUUCCCCAAAUGUAUUUUUCCAAGUGCUUGUACCCUGGUGUCCAUUAAGGGAAAUGUACUCCAUAUGUUUCUAAUUCUUCUACCCUGAAAUGAUCAAAAUAUUAUAUUGCUGAGAUCUCUGAAGACUAGAAAGAUCCUUUUCAAUUUUUUUUUUCUCUUUGAUGACACUAACAGAAAUGGGUGAUCCCAGUAAUCACAAAGAGGCUCAAAUUCACUCCCAAAUGCCCGGCCACCAAGAAGCUUUGGACAUAAGUAUUUUUUGGGGGUAUUUGUGCCAACUGCUGUUUUAGGACAUGUUUCUGAUAAUGCUUUACACUUACCAGAAAAGCUGUUUUUGAAAAAUCCAGUGUUGUCUUACAAUCAUUAAUUUAAAAAAAAAAAGUUUCCCAAGUAUUUUCUUAGAGCAAGGAGAUCUCUUUCUGAUGAAGAAUACACUCUAGCCUAAAAAGCCACUUAGGUGGACCAGUUUCUUUGAUUAACAAAAGUUACAAAGGGGAAAAGAAGAGUGUUAGAGAGGAUACCUGUAACAAAAAGAGACAGGAGACAUAUGGAACACUCGUGGUGUGUCACCCUUAUUUGAACCCUCAUUCAAACAACAACUGUUAAGAAAAGUAAAACAUAGGAGGCAUAUAUCAAUACAGAAUGGCUAUAUGAUGAUAUUAAGGAAUUAUUCUUUUUAAUUAUGAUAUUGAUAAUUAGCUAUUUUUUGAAAGAUACCUCCUUUUAUAGAUACAUGCUGAAAUAUUUACAGAAAAAUUUUUUAAAAGCCUGGAAUUUGUUUAAAAAGAAUCAGGGUGUGGUAUAGUUAAAACUCCUCCCUCCCUCCAUCUCUCCCUCUCCCCCUCUCUCCCUCUCCCCCUCUCUCCCUCUCUCCUUUUCUCCUUCCCUCACUCCCUUUUCUUCUUUUUUCCCUCCCCUCCUCCUUCCCCUCCUUUCUCCCCCACUGCCCCAGCUUCUCUUCCCUUCUGUUCUCUUUUUCUGGCCUUCAUUUGGGCUGACAAGAAGAGGAUGCAUGUUUUAUAUCAGGUUGGCAGGUAUACUUGAGAUAUAUUGUCUUGGCAAUACAAAGGCCUGACACUUCCUAGGGACCCAGAUGGGUAUUGUAGAUGUUUAGGGCAUGCCUUGACCUCUGAGUAGCCUUCUUGGGCUUGAGGUCUCAUUUGACUAGACUACCACUCCACAGUCAGCCACUGUGGUCUGUUUUUUAAAAACGUUGCCAUGAUGAGAAUGUGAAGGAUUUGGGUUGAAGUUAAGGACACUUCCUUUUUAUUAUUAGUCUGGAGUUUUAAAGGAGAUACCUGGGAUCCCACCCUUACUUUGUUACUUUGAUUUGGAGUCAGCCCUUGGCUUUGAGAGUGUGCUGUGAUAUUGGUCUGAUUUAAUCAUUGCCUAUGUAGAAAAAGAGAUUAGAUCACUGGAUCCCAAACUAGCCUCAGAAAGUAAGUCAUUGAUGGCAAGAAUCACCUGGAGAGAUUUUCAGUUUAAUUCUUAAAAAAUUUAGUGACGAUACUUGGAUAACCCUCUGGGAAUUCUGAUUCAGUAGUCCUGGGUAGAAAUAGAAUCUAAAUAUCUGUAAUUUUAUCAGGUUUCUACACGAUUCUCAUGUUCCAAUAGUUUGGUGAUUUACCAGGUUCAAUGCCUUUUAAUAGAUUCAGUUGCUCAGGAGCAGAUUGAGGUUGUAUUUCCAUAUAGUCCUACCUUGUAAAAAAUGGAUGUGUCAAGUUUUUUGUUGGUGUUAUUGUUUUUAAUUGUUAUUUUGACUUGCUGGGCUGGGCGUGGUGAUUCACGCCAGUAGUCCCAGCAACUUUGGGAGGCUGAAUUGGGUGGAUUGCUUGAGCCCAGGAGUUUGAGACCAGCCUGGGCAACAUGGAAAAACCGAUCUGUACUAAAAAACUGGAAAAUUAGCCAGGUGAGGUAGUGCGUGCCUUUAGUCCCAGCUACUCAGGAGGCUGAGGUAGGAGGACUGCUUGAGCCCAGGAGGUUGAGGCUGCAGUGAGCUGUGAUCAUGCGCUGCACUCCGAUUUGGGUGACAGCGAGACCCUGUCUCAAAGGAAAAAAAAAAAAAAGGUUACUUGCUUAUGAAUAAGACCUUCCAUAUAGCAGUUAUUAUAUAAGCACUAGGUAAAUAUUAAUAAAUGGCAAAUACUAAAAGGAAAGACAGGAAAAGGAAAGGCAACUGAUAUUUAUUGAAGGCCUACUAUUAUAGUAAACUUGACUCAUAAUUUAUAUUUUCUUCUUUAAUUUUAACCUUGGCAUGCAAUGAUUAUUACCCAAUUUUGUAUUCAGUAAAAUUAAAGCCCAGAGAAGUUUAGUAUUUUUCCUAGAGUCACAUAGUAAACACGUGGCAGCAGGGGUGUUUGGAUACUAUUGUGCCAGGCAGCCUUUCCGAACACUCCAGCCUAUUUCUCAAUUCUUUCUUGGCUCCAGAGGAUUGUGUAGCAGGAGGGGAAAUCUGUUCAGAGAUCAGGAAACUGGACCAAUUGGGCAAGCUGCCAGAGCUUCCUUUACUGGAUUGUACCAGCAAGUUUGUUUUUCUCUGUCCAAUACUGGGUAAAGGUCCCACCGAAAGCCUUUGUCUCUGCUCAGAAUGCCUGGUAUGAUCUCUGGGAAACUAUUUGGCAAAGGAGUGUGGCAGCUGAAGCACAGAAGCCUCUCCUAGGUGGUUCACCCAUAUCUGAUUUUUUUUUCUUUGGCACCUUGUAACAGACCUGAGAAUGUUGAAAUUUUGUGCCAACGUGGACACCAUUCAGCAUGUCAGAUUUCUCUGAUACCGUGAAGAUCAAUAUGUUGGAUGCAAAGGAAAAGUCCCAGCAAUAGAUUCCAGCCCUCACUGCCACUUACCUGGUAUAUUACAACAGCCUCCAUACUGGUCUUCCUAUCUGCAGCCUGUCCUCUGCUUUCCGGCCCACUUUUCUCAGGGGGAUCCUCUUUCAAAUAAAGGUCUGAUUAUGUUCCUCCAAUAUUAAACCCCUUCAGUGACUCCCCAGUUCUUGAGGAAAAAAUGCUGAGUCUCUGAGCAUAGCACUGAAUACCCUUCCUGGUCUGGCCCUGUUUCUCCGCAUGCUUCUCCCACUCCACCCAGCUUCUGGCAGGUCAUACUACCGUGGCUCACCAAAGAUGCCUUGGAAACCAGGUACUUUCAUGUCUCUGUUUCUCCAGCUGGAGUUUCGUUCCUUCUUUGACCUGCCUGGCAAACUCCUAUGCAUUCUUUGAUUCCUACUCCUUCAUGAAGCCUUUCAGCAGUUUCUUUCUUAGCACAACUCUACCACCUUGUCUCACCUGUUCACAGACAUCUGCCUGCCUCCCUCUCUAGGCUAUGGUGCCCUCCAAGGGGAGGCAAGGUGUUGUUUUCAAAUCAUUCACAGUACUUACUACAUAGGCCACUUACAGUCAGUGUGUAAUAACUGAAGGAGGACUUGAGUGAAUAGGCAAAUAAAGAUGGUUACCAUGAUAGGCCGAGAUCUGAAAAGAAGCUAAUAAUCAAUGCAUGAAGAUGUGUGAGGAACUUGUGUGUCUUCAGUACCAUUCUAAAUACCAUACAAAUACAGGUGCCGCCAGAGUGCUUGCACAUGGCAGCUUCACAGCCCAUUUGAGAAGUAGAAUUAAUACAUGUGAAGAAUGAGGCCGGGCACUGUGGCUCACGCCUGUAAUCCCAGCACUCUGGGAGGCCGAGGCAGGCGAAUCAUGAGGUCAAGAGAUUGAAACUGUCCUGCUCAACAUGGUGAAACCCCGUCUCUAUUAAAAAUACAAAAAUUAGCUGGACGUGGUGGCACACGCCUGUAAUUCCAGCUACUCGGGAAGCUGAGGCAGGAGAAUCGCUUGAACCCGAGAGGCAGAGGUUGCAGUGAGCCAAAAUCGCGCCACUGCACUCCAGCCUGGCGACAGAGUGAGACUCUGUCUCUUAAAAAAUAAAUAAAUAAAAUAAAAGAAUGAGUAAGAAAACCAAGAAAAUAUGCAAUUUAGUUCAGCUUGUUUGGUGCUGGUAAUACUUUAUUUUUCAUGUGUCGAUUUUUGAUCUCCACCUUGCACUGUGAGCUCCCUGAGGACAGGGACUUUGUCUUGGCAAUUAUGUCUUCACACUUGGCAUACAGUCAGUUUUCAAGAUAUGUUUGUUCAAUGAAUAAAUGGAUGGUAGGCACCAUUCAGUGCUGUUUAGGGUCAAAGGAAGGCAUGAUUUGUGUGGGUUGAAGUGGUCAAGGAGGGCUUCACACAUAAGCCAGUUAUGAAGGAUAUAGGCAUUGAAGAAGCACUAAAACUGGUUGUGAGCUUUACUCUUCAGAGAGUCACAGUUUUAGAAAAGCUCUUGCUCUAUUGGAAAGAAUAUGGGUUUUAGACCAAAUACAUCUAGAAUCAAAUUUGGACUCUUUCCCUUAUCUGCUAUGUGAUCUUGAGAUCUCUGAGUUUCAGUUUCCUUGCCCAUAAAAUGAAAUCAAUAUUACUUCCCUUAGAAUAUGCUUGUGAGCCGUAAAAGCGAUAUCAUAUAUAAAGCAUGUAGCAUAAUGCCUAGCGUACAUUAGGCUCUCAAUAAAUGGUAAGUAAAAGCUGAUAUAUAGGUAUAGUGUGUCUGAAAUACCUGGGAAACAUGGAUUAUUUGGAUGACGUAGUAACAUUUGAUUAAAUUUGCAUGAUUAUUAUAUUGGCACAUAACAAUUAGAAUUAUAAUAGAUUCCAGUAUUUUUAUGGCCUUUUAAGUGUGUUUUGGGGAUUUCUAUCACAUUUCUUUACUUUUUUAACAUUGGAAAAUUGGAAAUGGAUAUUUGCCCCCAAAUUGUCUGAUAUAUAGAUCUCGCCCUUCCCAUUACACUUGUGAAGGGAAGGCUUUUCUGGCAGGAGGAGCAUAAUGCGUAGAGGAGGGAAAGGGAAAUGAGCUUUCCAUUUUGGGAGAAAAAUUAGAGCUACUCUUCCAGUGACAAACCGCAUUGCCUGGCUUUCCUUCUGCAGGCUCUGCCUCAUGCCUGUGUUCCUAUAGACAUUGGAGUUAAAGCUCUCAUUCAUGGUCAUGAUUCUCGCCUCUGUCUAAUUCUUUUACUUUGUCGUGUACCAUCUCUCCUUUUCCCACUGUUUUUUCCAGCCACCUCUGUUUCUUUUGGUUUCCUUGAGCAUGUCAAGUUCUUUUCUGGCCUAUGUUCUUUGAAUUUACUGUUCCCUUUGACAGACAUUCUUUUCCUCUGGCUCUUUUCAUUUUUCAGAAAAUCAGCUGACUCCUUACCCUGUGGUGGUAUUGGAGCCAAAUAAUGGAAUUGAUUUUUCAGUGUUUAUUCCACAUAAUUCCAAGGAAUAUGAUUUUAAGAGUGUUCACAAUUCAUAUUUUUUUUUAAUUUUUGAAAUUGAAUAAGUUUCAAAUACGAAAAUUUAGGAACAUGAUACAAAACUUUUCUCUGUGCACCACUGGAGUACUGCUUUUGAAAUCAAUUCUCUCUGUCCUGGAUUACCCUUAGAGCUCCUGUCUCCUGCAUGGAGGAGGGUGGAGGGCAUUUAACAUGUCCAUCUCUCACCCCAUUCUACCUGAGCUUCCAGCACCACCACCUCUGGGCAGUUCCGCUUUUAGUCAGCAGCUCCCAGUUCCCAUAAUUUUGACUUCUGUCCUUGCUAGUCCAGAAGAAAUGGCUCUUCUGGGAUUGAAUUCCUCCCUUUCCCCAGCAGAAAUGGAUUGGGGCAGAGGAAUUGCGGAGCUCCAUGGCAUAGAGGGUCCUGGAAGGCUUGUCAUUAGGGUAUCCAGGGUGGGAAGGGGAGUGAAGGGAGGGGAAGGAGGAAGGAAUUGAGUUGGGAAGAGUCAAGGAGGAUGAAUGAAGUUGCUGACUGAUGUCUGGAAUAACAUUAUUUCACCCUCAAAAAUACCAGUAAUUCAGGACUGAAAAAUAAAUUUCACAAUAUGUUUUAAUUUCAAAAAGUGAUAGUGUAUUUGACAUUCUUAUCCAGCCUGGUCUCACCUCAGGAGUUCCCCCAUUGGAGAGGCCAUCCCUGAAUUUCUAACUCACAGGCCUCCCCUACGUUAAUAUAUUUAUGUCCUCCUGGCCCUUGUUUACUUUUUACUUGUUUACUUUUGCUUUUGUUUACUUGUUUACUUUUGCUCCAUGAAGUCAGGGACCUGCCUGCUUGCUCCGCAAUCCCUAGAACUGUGUCUAGAACCUUAGUUGGUUGCAGUAAAUAUUUGUUGAAUGGAUGGAUGAGAUGGUUGUAGCAAUCUAAGUUGCUUUGGAUGAGAUUAACACUGAAAAAAAAAAAAAAACUGGUUGCCUGCAAUUCUGUCAGCCAGUCCAGGCAAUGCUAAUACAGCUUUGAUUAUUAUGAUCAUGAUUAUUAUUUUGUUUUGAAACCUUUUUCAGAGGCCAAGCAUGCUGGGGACUUGAGGGACAUAAAAAUCUUUCAACUGAUUAUGCCACCUGCAAACAGGAUAAGCCUGACUUUCUACCUCACCCACCUCUUGCUAUCACAGAUAUGAAUCAACGAACACACAAAAAAGGUUUUCAAUUCUCCCUUUGGAAAGAGGGCACAUUUAAUAUUCUGAGUCAGGCAAGGAAAGACUCUAGCCACAAAGACAGCUGGGAACUCAGGUCCAUAGCAGGCACCCAGGACGGAGGUGAAGAGAAGGCGCCUCCCUGUCUGGUGACAGCAGCUGGGGCCCUUGCUGCCUCCCUCCCCACAAAAAUCCAGUUGGGACCAGUGCAUGCUGGGAAUCUGCCUGCCUGACAGAAACAGAUGGCCUCAGGUGGUGACUGAUCUCUUGGUGACACUAACUGCAUAGCUGCUGCUUUACUCAUGACCGAAUGAGACACGAGAUGGCGGAGGUCUCUCUGCUCCCUGGUGUGUAAGUGGACAUAUUCAGCAGAGAAAGGCUGGGACGACAGUUUCUGGAAAAUGAUUGGUUUGGAAGACUUUGUUGCAGAUAAUUACAGCAAAAUAGGAAACCAAGUGCUACCUCCUGGAGCUUCUCUUGGAAAUGGGCUCACACCAGAGGCAGCAAGAGACCUUGGCCUUCUCCCUGGGAUUGCGGUCGCAGCUUCACUCAUUGAUGCCCAUGCAGGAGGACUAGGAGUGAUUGGGGCAGAUGUGAGAGGGCACGGCCUCAUCUGUGAGGGGCAGCCAGUGACGUCACGGCUGGCUGUCAUCUGUGGAACGUCUUCUUGUCACAUGGGGAUCAGCAAAGACCCGAUUUUUGUACCAGGCGUCUGGGGGCCUUAUUUCUCAGCCAUGGUACCUGGGUUCUGGCUGAAUGAAGGUGGUCAGAGCGUUACUGGAAAAUUGAUAGACCACAUGGUACAAGGCCAUGCUGCUUUUCCAGAACUACAAGUAAAGGCCACAGCCAGAUGCCAGAGUAUAUAUGCAUAUUUGAACAGUCACCUGGAUCUGAUUAAGAAGGCUCAGCCUGUGGGUUUCCUUACUGUUGAUUUACAUGUUUGGCCAGAUUUCCAUGGCAACCGGUCUCCCUUAGCAGAUCUGACACUAAAGGGCAUGAGAACCACUGGAUAUCUGUAUAUUCCGGCUUUGGCAGCGUUGCACUCUCCCAGUUCUCUACUCUCCCCUCAGGUCACCGGAUUGAAACUGUCUCAGGACCUUGAUGAUCUUGCCAUUCUCUACCUGGCCACAGUUCAAGCCAUUGCUUUGGGGACUCGCUUCAUUAUAGAAGCCAUGGAGGCAGCAGGGCACUCAAUCAGUACUCUUUUCCUAUGUGGAGGCCUCAGCAAGAAUCCCCUUUUUGUGCAAAUGCAUGCGGACAUUACUGGCAUGCCUGUGGUCCUGUCGCAAGAGGUGGAGUCCGUUCUUGUGGGUGCUGCUGUUCUGGGUGCCUGUGCCUCAGGGGAUUUCGCUUCUGUACAGGAAGCAAUGGCAAAAAUGAGCAAAGUUGGGAAAGUUGUGUUCCCGAGACUACAGGAUAAAAAAUACUAUGAUAAGAAAUACCAAGUAUUCCUGAAGCUGGUUGAACACCAGAAGGAGUAUUUGGCGAUCAUGAAUGAUGACUGAACAGGGCUUGCAGGUGCUGAUGCCAGAAGCUUCUGUGCCAUUGCAUUAAAGACUUGUCAUUUGAUCCAUGUUCAAGACCCUUGAGGUAUUGUUUCAUCAUUUCUGUAUUGUCUUUCAAUAAAGAAAACAAACAUGUGCAACCAGAA